CUCUUGUGUAGCCUGAGGCGGCGGUAGCAUGGAGGGGGAGAGUACGUCGGCGGUGCUCUCGGGCUUUGUGCUCGGCGCACUCGCUUUCCAGCACCUCAACACGGACUCGGACACGGAAGGUUUUCUUCUUGGGGAAGUAAAAGGUGAAGCCAAGAACAGCAUUACUGAUUCCCAAAUGGAUGAUGUUGAAGUUGUUUAUACAAUUGACAUUCAGAAAUAUAUUCCAUGCUAUCAGCUUUUUAGCUUUUAUAAUUCUUCAGGCGAAGUAAAUGAGCAAGCACUGAAGAAAAUAUUAUCAAAUGUCAAAAAGAAUGUGGUAGGUUGGUACAAAUUCCGUCGUCAUUCAGAUCAGAUCAUGACGUUUAGAGAGAGGCUGCUUCACAAAAACUUGCAGGAGCAUUUUUCAAACCAAGACCUUGUUUUUCUGCUAUUAACACCAAGUAUAAUAACAGAAAGCUGCUCUACUCAUCGACUGGAACAUUCCUUAUAUAAACCUCAAAAAGGACUUUUUCACAGGGUACCUUUAGUGGUUGCCAAUCUGGGCAUGUCUGAACAACUGGGUUAUAAAACUGUAUCAGGUUCCUGUAUGUCCACUGGUUUUAGCCGAGCAGUACAAACACACAGCUCUAAAUUUUUUGAAGAAGAUGGAUCCUUAAAGGAGGUACAUAAGAUAAAUGAAAUGUAUGCUUCAUUACAAGAGGAAUUAAAGAGUAUAUGCAAAAAAGUGGAAGACAGUGAACAAGCAGUAGAUAAACUAGUAAAGGAUGUAAACAGAUUAAAACGAGAAAUUGAGAAAAGGAGAGGAGCACAGAUUCAGGCAGCAAGAGAGAAGAACAUCCAAAAAGACCCUCAGGAGAACAUUUUUCUUUGUCAGGCAUUACGGACCUUUUUUCCAAAUUCUGAAUUUCUUCAUUCAUGUGUUAUGUCUUUAAAAAAUAGACAUGUUUCUAAAAGUAGCUGUAACUACAACCACCAUCUCGAUGUAGUAGACAAUCUGACCUUAAUGGUAGAACACACUGACAUUCCUGAAGCUAGUCCAGCUAGUACACCACAAAUCAUUAAGCAUAAAGCCUUAGACUUAGAUGACAGAUGGCAAUUCAAGAGAUCUCGGUUGUUAGAUACACAAGACAAACGAUCUAAAGCAGAUACUGGUAGUAGUAACCAAGAUAAAGCAUCCAAAAUGAGCAGCCCAGAAACAGAUGAAGAAAUUGAAAAGAUGAAGGGUUUUGGUGAAUAUUCACGGUCUCCUACAUUUUGAUCCUUUUAACCUUACAAGGAGAUUUUUUUAUUUGGCUGAUGGGUAAAGCCAAACAUUUCUAUUGUUUUUACUAUGUUGAGCUACUUGCAGUAAGUUCAUUUGUUUUUACUAUGUUCACCUGUUUGCAGUAAUACACAGAUAACUCUUAGUGCAUUUACUUCACAAAGUACUUUUUCAAACAUCAGAUGCUUUUAUUUCCAAACCUUUUUUUCACCUUUCACUAAGUUGUUGAGGGGAAGGCUUACACAGACACAUUCUUUAGAAUUGGAAAAGUGAGACCAGGCACAGUGGCUCACACCUGUAAUCCCAGCACUUAGGGAAGACAAGUCAGGAGGAUUGAUUGAAGUUAGGAGUUAGAGACCAGCCUGGGCAACGUAUUGAGACCAUGUCUAUUAAAAAAUAAAAUGGAAAAGCAAGAAUAGCCUUAUUUUCAAAAUAUGGAAAGAAAUUUAUAUGAAAAUUUAUCUGAGUCAUUAAAAUUCUCCUUAAGUGAUACUUUUUUAGAAGUACAUUAUGGCUAGAGUUGCCAGAUAAAAUGCUGGAUAUCAUGCAAUAAAUUUGCAAAACAUCAUCUAAAAUUUAAAUUUGUCCUACAUUUGUACUUGCUAAAUCUGGCAGCCUUAAUUAUUACACAACUAUAACACAACACAAACAGUAAUCUCUCCCCUAGUUUAGAGUCCUUUGCAUGAAAUUUAGCAAAUCUAUCAUUUUGAAUACAGUACAAGCCUGGUAAUCCAGUGUAUUUGGGAUAGGCCAGUGGAACUCAGAACUGAUACAUAUAUACAUGUAUGUCUAUCAUAUUCAAUGUCUAUUAGGUGUAAAUCAUCUCUUCAUGUAAAAGACACUACUGGUUUGAGGGUAGACUCGUCUAGGAAUAUUUUGUCCUUCUGUGACAGCACCACUAUCCAUCCCAAUGUAACAUUUCUACAAAGGGAAGAUAUCUUAACCAGGCAUACUUAUAUUUGCUAGUUGGAAAAUCAUUCUGAACAGUUUUAAUUCCAUUCUAUUGAAUGGAUUAUUGUAUGAGCUAUUUGGGGAUCAGAUAUAAAUGACAAUCACACAGAACCACUUUUAUUCAACAUAGAUAAAAUGUGAUGAGUGUUAACAUUUUAAAUAAGCAAUCUGCUUAAUGGACAUUGGUAUGAAGGGGAAGUGUCAUUCUUUACCUCACUCCUCAAACACUUUUCUAUCCAAAGGUUGGUUUGAGUCAGUAUUGGCAUCAUACAACCACUUACUGUAAAAUAAGUUUAUUAGUGGUAACGUGAUAGAAUUUAUUCCCGAUAUCUGAUGUUACAAACUUUAGGGUCCUUGAGAUAUGCAGGAUCCUUGUAUGUAACUGGCAUAAACCCUGUAAAGAGAUAAUUAAAGUUCUUGACAAAACAUAAUGAGCAAAAUUUCAGCUAGCUCAAUUCAGUUGUUGAGGUAUUCUUUCUUACCCAUUAUUUGAGCUCUCUUAAUUGCUUUUGUGAUUUCUUUCUGUUUCUUCCCACAAAGACCUGUAAAAUAAAAAGCUUUCUUAUUCAUAAAAAAUGUCAAUAUUUAAAGUUUGCAAUUUUUUUUUUUGAGAUGGAGUCUCCCUGUGUCACCCAGGCUGGAGUACAGUGGUGCUCUCUCGCCUCACUGCAACCUCCGCCACCCAGGCUCAAUCGAUUAUCUUGCCUCAGCCUCCUUAGUAACUGGAAUUACAGGCAUGCACCGCCACACCCGGAUAAUUUUUUUGUAUUUGUAGUAGAAACGGGGUUUCACCAUAUUGGCCAGGCUGGUCCUGAACUCCUGGCCUCAGGUGAUCUGCCCACCUCAGCCUCCCAAAGUGCUGGGAUUACAGGUGUGAGCCAACAUGCCCAGCCUCAACAAGUUUUUAAGUCAAGGAUUGGUAAAUCAUUUUUGUCAAGGGCCACAAUAAUAAUCUAGGUUUUGUGGGCCAUACAGUCUCCAUCACUGCCACUCAACUCUGCUGUUGUAGCUCGAAAACAACCAUAUGGCACUACGUAAACAAAACUACAAAAACAAGUGGGGUUGGGUGCAGUGGCUCACACCUGUAAUCCCAGCACUUUGGGAGGCCUAGGCAGGUGGAUCACCUGAGGUCAGGAAUUCAAGACCAGCCUGGCCAACAUGGAGAAACCCAAUCUCUAAAAAUACAAAAAUUAGCCAGGCGUGGUGGUGCAUGCCUGUAAUCCCAGCUAUUCGGGAGGCUGAAGCAUGAGAAUCACUUGAACCCAGGAGGCAGAGGUUGCAGUGAGCCGAGAUUGUGCCACAGCACUCCAGCCUGGGUGACAGUGAGAUUCCAUCUCAAAAAAAAAAAAAAGUGGCAUUUGUAUAUGAUGAACCUAAUCAAGAUAAAAAGGGAGCAGGUCGAAUUUGGCCUAUGGGCCAUAGUUUGCUGACACCAAGUUUAAGUAUCAAUCUAGGAAUGAUUAUAGUAUAUUCCAAAACAUCAACAACAGUUUUUUAAAGCCCAGUUUUUCUAUAUAGUUAACUCUGCAUAAGACAGCAAAAUAAUAAUCCUCUUGGCCUAAGAGACUUUUUCAUAGUAACUAGCUCUAGUCCCUGUAGUAUCUGAUCUAGUAGUAAUUUAUAGCACAAUUUGAAAAUUUGAGUUUUCUUAAAUGAUAGAAAUAGAUUGAUAUAAUUCGUAUCUACAUUUAUAUUCCCAUAAUAAAAAAGAACAUACCUGUAAUGUGCCUUCCAUAAAUGCAUCCAGUAAAUGGAGAAACAAACUGGGACAAAAGCUGUUUUGGAGUUUUAUGUGGAGGGGAAAAAAAAGUAUCUGUUAUUUAUUUCUGAAUGUGUAAAUUUCAAAAAACAACCUUCAGGUUAUAUAAAGCUUUACUAAAUUUCAGACACAUUUCAUAAAAUAUAAGAAAAAAAUAUUGUUAUCCUCCUGUUACCUUUUAAAUAUUUUCUAUCCAGUGUGUCAAGUCUAUAUAUAAUUAAACAGCAGAUUAAUCAGCA